CCUGGAUGAACAUCACCCACGCCUAUUCCCAGGGCCACCAGAAGCUGAAUUUGGAUACAGUGUCUUACAACAUGUUGGGGGUGGACAGCGAUGGUGAGGAAGAAACCGGAGUGCCAGGGGAUUGGGACUGCAGUAGUGCUAACAAAGGGGAGGCAAGAUAGAUGGGACUCUAAACUAAUCUGGUCUUUUGAAAGUGGCUGGGGCUCUAAACUUACCACCUCCAUGCUCUUUCCCUUUGGCCUAUGUCAAGGGUCAUGUUUGCCCUGUGCUUACUUACAUUCACAUCCUCUUCCCAGGAUGCUGGUGGGCGCCCCCUGGGAUGGGCCUUCAGGCGACCGGAGGGGGGACGUUUAUCGCUGCCCUGUAGGGGGGGCCCACAAUGCCCCAUGUGCCAAGGGCCACUUAGGUGACUACCAACUGGGAAAUUCAUCUCAUCCUGCUGUGAAUAUGCACCUGGGGAUGUCUCUGUUAGAGACAGAUGGUGAUGGGGGAUUCAUGGCCUGUGCCCCUCUCUGGUCUCGUGCUUGUGGCAGCUCUGUCUUCAGUUCUGGGAUAUGUGCCCGUGUGGAUGCUUCAUUCCAGCCUCAGGGAAGCCUGGCACCCACUGCCCAACGCUGCCCAACAUACAUGGAUGUUGUCAUUGUCUUGGAUGGCUCCAACAGCAUCUACCCCUGGUCUGAAGUUCAGACCUUCCUACGAAGACUGGUAGGGAAACUGUUUAUUGACCCAGAACAGAUACAGGUGGGACUGGUACAGUAUGGGGAGAGCCCUGUACAUGAGUGGUCCCUGGGAGAUUUCCGAACGAAGGAAGAAGUGGUGAGAGCAGCAAAGAACCUCAGUCGGCGGGAGGGACGAGAAACAAAGACUGCCCAAGCAAUAAUGGUGGCCUGCACAGAAGGGUUCAGUCAGUCCCAUGGGGGCCGACCCGAGGCUGCCAGGCUACUGGUGGUUGUCACUGAUGGAGAGUCCCAUGAUGGAGAGGAGCUUCCUGCAGCACUAAAGGCCUGUGAGGCUGGAAGAGUGACACGCUAUGGGAUUGCAGUCCUUGGUCACUACCUCCGGCGGCAGCGAGAUCCCAGCUCUUUCCUGAGAGAAAUUAGAACUAUUGCCAGUGAUCCAGAUGAGCGAUUCUUCUUCAAUGUCACAGAUGAGGCUGCUCUGACUGACAUUGUGGAUGCACUAGGAGAUCGGAUUUUUGGCCUUGAAGGGUCCCAUGCAGAAAACGAAAGCUCCUUUGGGCUGGAAAUGUCUCAGAUUGGUUUCUCCACUCAUCGGCUAAAGGAUGGGAUUCUUUUUGGGAUGGUGGGGGCCUAUGACUGGGGAGGCUCUGUGCUAUGGCUUGAAGGAGGCCACCGCCUUUUCCCCCCACGAAUGGCACUGGAAGACGAGUUCCCCCCUGCAUUGCAGAACCAUGCAGCCUACCUGGGUUACUCUGUUUCUUCCAUGCUUUUGCGGGGUGGACGCCGCCUGUUUCUCUCUGGGGCUCCUCGAUUUAGACAUCGAGGAAAAGUCAUCGCCUUCCAGCUUAAGAAAGAUGGGGCUGUGAGGGUUGCCCAGAGCCUCCAGGGGGAGCAGAUUGGUUCAUACUUUGGCAGUGAGCUCUGCCCAUUGGAUACAGAUAGGGAUGGAACAACUGAUGUCUUACUUGUGGCUGCCCCCAUGUUCCUGGGACCCCAGAACAAGGAAACAGGACGUGUUUAUGUGUAUCUGGUAGGCCAGCAGUCCUUGCUGACCCUCCAAGGAACACUUCAGCCAGAACCCCCCCAGGAUGCUCGGUUUGGCUUUGCCAUGGGAGCUCUUCCUGAUCUGAACCAAGAUGGUUUUGCUGAUGUGGCUGUGGGGGCGCCUCUGGAAGAUGGGCACCAGGGAGCACUGUACCUGUACCAUGGAACCCAGAGUGGAGUCAGGCCCCAUCCUGCCCAGAGGAUUGCUGCUGCCUCCAUGCCACAUGCCCUCAGCUACUUUGGCCGAAGUGUGGAUGGUCGGCUAGAUCUGGAUGGAGAUGAUCUGGUCGAUGUGGCUGUGGGUGCCCAGGGGGCAGCCAUCCUGCUCAGCUCCCGGCCCAUUGUCCAUCUGACCCCAUCACUGGAGGUGACCCCACAGGCCAUCAGUGUGGUUCAGAGGGACUGUAGGCGGCGAGGCCAAGAGGCAGUCUGUCUGACUGCAGCCCUUUGCUUCCAAGUGACCUCCCGUACUCCUGGUCGCUGGGAUCACCAAUUCUACAUGAGGUUCACCGCAUCACUGGAUGAAUGGACUGCUGGGGCACGUGCAGCAUUUGAUGGCUCUGGCCAGAGGUUGUCCCCUCGGAGGCUCCGGCUCAGUGUGGGGAAUGUCACUUGUGAGCAGCUACACUUCCAUGUGCUGGAUACAUCAGAUUACCUCCGGCCAGUGGCCUUGACUGUGACCUUUGCCUUGGACAAUACUACAAAGCCAGGGCCUGUGCUGAAUGAGGGCUCACCCACCUCUAUACAAAAGCUGGUCCCCUUCUCAAAGGAUUGUGGCCCUGACAAUGAAUGUGUCACAGACCUGGUGCUUCAAGUGAAUAUGGACAUCAGAGGCUCCAGGAAGGCCCCAUUUGUGGUUCGAGGUGGCCGGCGGAAAGUGCUGGUAUCUACAACUCUGGAGAACAGAAAGGAAAAUGCUUACAAUACGAGCCUGAGUCUCAUCUUCUCUAGAAACCUCCACCUGGCCAGUCUCACUCCUCAGAGAGAGAGCCCAAUAAAGGUGGAAUGUGCCGCCCCUUCUGCUCAUGCCCGGCUCUGCAGUGUGGGGCAUCCUGUCUUCCAGACUGGAGCCAAGGUGACCUUUCUGCUAGAGUUUGAGUUUAGCUGCUCCUCUCUCCUGAGCCAGGUCUUCGUGAAGCUGACUGCCAGCAGUGACAGCCUGGAGAGAAAUGGGACCCUUCAAGAUAACACAGCCCAGACCUCAGCCUACAUCCAAUAUGAGCCCCACCUCCUGUUCUCUAGUGAGUCUACCCUGCACCGCUAUGAGGUUCACCCAUAUGGGACCCUCCCAGUGGGUCCUGGCCCAGAAUUCAAAACCACUCUCAGGGUUCAGAACCUAGGCUGCUAUGUGGUCAGUGGCCUCAUCAUCUCAGCCCUCCUUCCAGCUGUGGCCCAUGGGGGCAAUUACUUCCUAUCACUGUCUCAAGUCAUCACUAACAAUGCAAGCUGCAUAGUGCAGAACCUGACUGAACCCCCAGGCCCACCUGUGCAUCCAGAGGAGCUUCAACACACAAACAGACUGAAUGGGAGCAAUACUCAGUGUCAGGUGGUGAGGUGCCACCUUGGGCAGCUGGCAAAGGGGACUGAGGUCUCUGUUGGACUAUUGAGGCUGGUUCACAAUGAAUUUUUCCGAAGAGCCAAGUUCAAGUCCCUGACGGUGGUCAGCACCUUUGAGCUGGGAACCGAAGAGGGCAGUGUCCUACAGCUGACUGAAGCCUCCCGUUGGAGUGAGAGCCUCUUGGAGGUGGUUCAGACCCGGCCUAUCCUCAUCUCCCUGUGGAUCCUCAUAGGCAGUGUCCUGGGAGGGUUGCUCCUGCUUGCUCUCCUUGUCUUCUGCCUGUGGAAGCUUGGCUUCUUUGCCCAUAAGAAAAUCCCUGAGGAAGAAAAAAGAGAAGAGAAGUUGGAGCAAUGAAUGUAGAAUAAGGGUCUAGAAAGUCCUCCCUGGCAGCUUCUUCAAGAGACUUGCAUAAAAGCAGAGGUUUGGGGGCUCAGAUGGGACAAGAAGCCGCCUCUGGACUAUCUCCCCAGACCAGCAGCCUGACUUGACUUUUGAGUCCUAGGGAUGCUGCUGGCUAGAGAUGAGGCUUUACCUCAGACAAGAAGAGCUGGCACCAAAACUAGCCAUGCUCCCACCCUCUGCUUCCCUCCUCCUCGUGAUCCUGGUUCCAUAGCCAACACUGGGGCUUUUGUUUGGGGUCCUUUUAUCCCCAGGAAUCAAUAAUUUUUUUGCCUAGGUGCCUGACUCCUUUCAGAUUCCCUCUUUAUCUUCCCUCACAGUUUGGAAAGGAUGAGGGUUAUCUUCCUCGAUUCUUCCACCCUCUCACUUUCCUGCCUGUUCCCCACUCCACAGGAGGGAGCUGACGUUGGCUUGAAAGGAGUAAAGUCAACAUCUGCUGCUUUCCUGUGGACUCUGGUGAUUCAUAGAGCCGGAUGGGGAGAGUCAACAGGAAAAAAGGAGGGAGGAGGAAAAGCCACAAGAGACAUUCUGUACAAUUCCAAGGAACAGAGAAGCCUUUAGACAGGCAACUGCCAUCCCCCCUGAAACCUGAGACCUGUAGUGCACUCGACCGCCCUCAGGUGUUGGUGAAACAGAGCUGCCCCCAGGCUCGCUGGGCAUAGGCUUCCUGAUUCCAAGCCUUUUCUGGGAGCAAAGCCAGGGCCUGGUGCCUGAUUUUCUGAAGCCAGGAGCCCUCAGGUGGCUGGAGCUGGAAUAGCAGGGAGGACUGGGUGUACCUAGGCAGUAUUUUCUCUACUUCUCUCAAGUCUUAUACUCACUCUUGAGCCCUCCUUGGGGCCUGCUUAGAAAGCAGACAGGAGAGAGAGUACUGCUACUUGAUGAUGGGAAAUGCUUUCACUUUACCAGCUUUGGGAAGCAGCAGCCCCAUGGGAUCUAAAAGUGUGGAGUCUGCAUUAAGAAACCUACAUGGGUGGCAUGGGGCUCUGGGGAGCAAGCCCUUACUUGCUCAGCACUGGUUAUGUAGCACAAAUAGCUCCUAGGAAAAUGUUUCUGGGGCAACCCUAGAACCCUGGUCAUAUUUUGCAGGGUUUCUCUGGUGGAAUCAGUUUGCCAGCCCUUGCUUGAUGCUUACUGGAAAUCUCCAGGUUAAUUUCUAUCUCUGAUCCCUCCCCAACCCACUCCAUAUUUGGGUCAUGGACAGUAAAGGCAGUUGGAUUCUCAUAGACAACUGGGUAACUUAUAUUUCUUUGUAAUCAAGACUUGAGAUAUCGAAGUCAGUUAUUGGUCUCCAGAGUGCAGCUCUGGGAGCCUUUUGAAGAAUCAGCACUCAUUAAGAGCUGAGAAGAGAGAAGACCUGAUUGGGUGGUUGACUAGCAGUCACAGAACCUGUCCUCCCAGGCUGUUCCUGAGGCCUGACCACAGUAUUUAUUUUGGCAUGUCUCUGGCCUUCUGCAGAGGCCCACCCUCAUGGGCAUUGUCUCUGUUUCCCAGUGGGGUGGACAGUAUAUCAGAUGGUCAGAACAAAUAAAGUUCAGUGUCAAAUGA